AACACGGUGUGCCGUCCGUGCGGGCCGGGCUUCUACAACGACGUGGUCAGCUCCAAGCCGUGCAAGCCCUGCACGUGGUGUAACCUCAGUGAGCUCCCACCUGGCCCCACAGCCCCACCCAGCACAGGGGGCGGCAGCCUGGCACCCACAUUCCCACGCAGCAGCAUGGGGCUCCCACAGCCGCAGAAACGAACCUCAAACCACAGCGGGGUCUGCUCCGCCACAGGGGUCCUUCGAGGAGCUGAGGCGUCUCCCAGGGGCACCCCCUCUCCCUCCGGGGGCCCAGACUCGGCCCAGGCCACGUGGAGUCGGGGAGACCACGCUGGCCAUGUGGCCUGGCCUUGCUGGCCUGAGCAGUGAGGCUGGGGGGUUGGGCCAUGGAGACCCUGCCGCAGGCGGGGCUGGCGGCUGGAGGCGGUGGAGGGGUAGGGAAGGGUGGCUGGGGCUGCCACGGAACCAGCCCCAGGUUGUGGCCAGGAAGGGAGGGCCCAGGAGCCUCGGGGGCUGCAGGGGCUCCAAGUCUCAGGGGAGGCCGCAGACCCCUGCCCACGGCCCUCUGUGUGGUGGGGAGGCCAACCUGUCCUCCAGUGCCCACGCUUCCUGAGGACCCUGUCCACAGCCCCCACCUGACCACCCCCCCAUCCGGCCCCUGCUCAGGAAGUGGGAGUGAGCGGAAGCAGCUGUGCACGGCCACACAGGACACAGUCUGCCGCUGCCGGGCGGGCACCCAGCCCCUGGACAGCUACAAGCCUGGAGUUGACUGUGCCCCCUGCCCUCCAGGGCACUUCUCCCCAGGCGACAACCAGGCCUGCAAGCCCUGGACCAACUGCACCUUGGCUGGGAAGCACACCCUGCAGCCGGCCAGCAAUAGCUCGGACGCAAUCUGUGAGGACAGGGACCCCCCAGCCACGCAGCCCCAGGAGACCCAGGGCCCCCCGGCCAGGCCCAUCACUGUCCAGCCCACUGAAGCCUGGCCCAGAACCUCACAGGGACCCUCCACCCGGCCCGUGGAGGUCCCCGGGGGCCGUGCGGUUGCCGCCAUCCUGGGCCUGGGCCUGGUGCUGGGGCUGCUGGGCCCCCUGGCCAUCCUGCUGGCCCUGUACCUGCUCCGGAGGGACCAGAGGCUGCCCCCCGAUGCCCACAAGCCCCCUGGUGAGUGCCUCAUGGCCCUGCCGCACUGCUCCUGGCGGGUGAGGCCCACCCACCAAUCUCUCCUUUUUUCCUCCCCAGGGGGAGGCAGUUUCCGGACCCCCAUCCAAGAGGAGCAGGCCGACGCCCACUCCACCCUGGCCAAGAUCUGACCUGGGCCCACCAAGGUGGACGCUGGGCCCCGCCAGGCUGGAGCCCGGAGGGUCUGCUGGGCGAGCAGGGCAGGUGCAGGCCGCCUGCCCCGCCACGCUCCUGGGCCAACUCUGCACCGUUCUAGGUGCCGAUGGCUGCCUCCGGCUCUCUGCUUACGUAUGCCAUGCAUACCUCCUGCCCCGCGGGACCACAAUAAAAACCUUGGCAGACGGGA